UUUCUCUUUUAGAAACUUUAAUGAGUUCAUUUCAUCCCUUCCUAGUAUAUUUGGACAAAAUGAAGUUAUCUUGCCAGCAAUGGCUCCUGAAUUCUAUGUCCUCUUCUUCAGUGCAUCUAGUUUUAUGGGUACGACUGGUCAGUGAAUUGCUGGUCACUGCCUAAAUGUCCUGGAAAUGGUAGGUGGUGAUGACACAAAGAACAUGCCAAGAUAUCCUGUGGCUGUAGCAAGAGUUUCAGAGAGAAAACUCAAGGAGUGAACUGUGUUUGGGUUGUUGAGGUAAUUGAGUGAGAGGAAAAGAUUUACAUUUCUAUCAUACAAGCCAGAGAAGCCAUUUUCCCAUGUAGGCCUUUAUGGUACUUCUAGUUUUAAGUGGGUACUUACAUUUUAAAAUGAGAAAGGUUGCCAUUCUCUUAGCUUACCUUGUAGGGCAGAAAACAUACUAGGAUUAUGAGAGAUGGAAUAGAAUUUUGAAUUUCAAACCAAUUAGGAACAGCUUGAAUAAAAUAGAACUUUCUUAUGACUCAGAGUGAAAGACCAUGCAAGGGCUAACAUUUGACAUUUCAGCAGCAAGCUUUUAGAGACAUUGUGUUAUGUAUUUGAAUUUCUUCUUCUCUGUGGGGAGUAAGGCCUUAGGACAUGCCAUUUAAUUACAUGUUUAAUGUGUUUUGUUUUAUAUUACCACAAAUUGGCUAAAACCAUUAUAAUGUGCUAAAACUUAUCCAUCUCUUCAAAAUCUAACCAUGUUGUUUAUAUUGAUAACUUCUUGAUAUUAUGAAUCCCACAAGCCAAGAAUACUUACAUGUUGCAAGAGAAACCUUCCUAAUUUGUUCACAAAUUUUCUGUUUUUUAAUUUCCUGAAAAAUUUCCUCAUUCUCUUUUUAUCGAUCUGGAAUAAAAUGAAGAAUUAAUAUGAUUGAGACUAUCUUCAUCUCUUCCUCUCUACCUUUUCAUUAAAAGGCAAUCAUUGCAGUGUCCUUUUAUAUGUAAAUUUUAUUUUUGCCUCUAACUAUCAUUUAGCUUUGUAGAAGCUAAAGCUUUAAAAUGGCAAAUAGAGGAAAUUUACAGAGAUGUAUUUUCAGUUUCUAUAGAACCUUCUUAAAAUUAGAUGACCAACCUCUACUCAAUGCUGAGAUUAUUCAUUAUGCUGUCAAUGUAUAAUUAUCUGUCGGUCUACUAUUUGUAAUUUCUCUGUGCUGAGAUAUCCCGUUUGCUAUUGAAUGCUACUUGAAAGAAAAUUAUUGAUCUAUACCACACAUAAGAGUUUUGAAAUCUUCCCAUCAGAGUAUAUUGCACCUUUAGCAUAAAAAAGGCUCUGAUUUAUUUUACUUUAUUUUUUUGCAAAUAGCUGCUUUAUAGUUCUUUAAGUUCAAUUCAAUAUUACUCUUUGUUAAACUUUAAAAAAGUCUUCAUUACUUUCCUUUGUUAAACCAUUUCUGCAUUCUUCAGAUAAUCCAGGAUGGUUUCAGUAAUUAAAAUAAUUUAGCUUCAUCACUGUUCAACAUAAUCACUGUUAAGCAUGUUAAUUCAGAUACUGAUCCUUAACAUUUUUGACUGUUAUGAUGGAGGCCUGGCCACAGACGUACCUUGUGCAUGUUUUUAAAAAACCUAACCUGUUAAUAAUCUACUCCAGGUUCUACCAGUAACCCAGGGGAUAUUUGUUUUCUUUUGUGGCUUCUUCCAAGGAAUCAUAUCAAAUUCCUUUGGAAAACUUGUAUUAUUUGCAUCCAUCGUCUACCCUUCUAUUUUAUACCCCCUAAAUAUUUAUAUCUACUAUGUACCUACAAAAAUUAAAAAUGAAAAAAAUUAAAAUUUAAUUUUAAACAUCUUGUAGUUGAGAAGCAAGUCGUCCAAUAUCAGAUUAUACUUAUAUAUACAUUAUAGUUAUGGCAAUGCCUUUAAUUUCAAUGCUUUUUUUUUUAGAAAUUCUGAACUAUCCAUGAAAGAUUUUGUUUUUUAUAAUUUUCCAUUAAGAGUGGGAUGUUAAAUAUGUUCUCUACUUUUUAUUUUAAAAAGGACAUCACUACAUGUCGUGAUAGUUUAUGUUUCAUGUGCAUUUAUGUUCUUCACCUUUAUGUUAUUCAGAAUUUAUUUUUGGUCCACAUAUGUGAUGUUAAAAUCUUAAGAUUUUUAAAGUUUACAAUAUGUAGAAUGUAGGUGUGUUACUGAAUCACUGUUGUACUGCAUUUGACAGCUUAUGUAUUUCUAAUAAAAUUAAAGACUUGGGAAGGAAGCAUAGAGGAUCAAGAAGAGACUAGGCUUUGGAAUAAGAUAAAUUUGGGAUUGAAUCCUGGCUUAUUUUCUUUUUCUGAGCUCUGGGAAAAAUCACAAACUCUAAAUUGCUGGAUUGUUCUAAGAAUUAACAGAGAUAACAUGGAGAGAUCCCUAAUAUAUAGCAGUACUUAAGUGUUUCCCCUACCUCCUUCAAGGUCAACUAAGUGAAAGAAAAGGUAAAUAUCAGAAAGAGGCAUCUUGGAGCAGUGCCCCGGGAUGUGAUGUUAUCAGCAGGAGUUACCAAACUGUGUAGCAGAAUGGACCACUUGGUGGUGUUUGGGACCUGGCAUGGUGGGAGAGGAGAGGAGAACCAGAGAGCAGGGCUUCAGACCACCCCUUCCCUGGUCUCCAGUGGUAUAGUGUGCUGUCUCUCAUUUUUCUUUAAAUGUGUUAAAUAAAUUGUGGUUUAUUCUGAUAAUUCUUUGAAAGAAAAAUGGCUUUAUCAUUUAAAGGGAAGAUAGUCAAGUGGCCAAAUAUAAAUAUACUCUGGAUCACUAAAUGUAACCGGUUUUAAAACUUUGUGUAGGAUGUAUUAAUACUUAAAAAAAUGAUGAGUUUUUCCCUCUUGAGUUUUUCCCUCUGGAAUGACCUUCAAAAGAGACUCAAAUCUCUGCUGUAGGUGAGGGACUGACCAAGUGGGUGGGCACAGUGGCAAAAUAUUGGUAGACAAAGUGAACAGAGGAAGAGUGGGGGUUAAAUUAGAUUUUACUAGGCAGCUGCCCUCUCCUUCCUACUUAAUGUGCUCAAGAGGAAUGAAGCCAACAUACCACUUAAAAGGGUUAGUCGGGGGAAAAUGACUCUUGAGGACCAGUAGCAAACCAGUUAGAAACCAGUGGUUUCUAACACCUGAAAACAUUCCUAGAAAUGAAAAGCAGUUAAGUCAGUGGAAAGAGAAAGGAGAGUAACACGUCUAAGACUAAGAUGUUCUUGGGGUUAAUCUAGGAAGUUGAAAAUCCGGAUUUGGAAGGCAAAGGGAACAGGACAACAAGGGUAGUUGUAGCCAUUACUUUAUUUUGGGCUAGAGUAAUUUUUGCUAAAUAAUGGCUUAUUAAAGGGUUCCUGAUGGUAGUUUGUGAUUGAUGUAGUGCCAACUCUUAUUUCUCAUCUGGACUGGGUAGCUGGUUAAAUAAUUUUUCUGUGACUUAAGUAAUUAUUUAGAAGUCAUGGUAACUAUUUGUCAAAAAGUAAAAUGAACCCAGCUCUCUCUGUAUGAGAUUCUGGAGUAGGUGUCUCCUUCAGAAUGCAACCCAUUUAGACUCAGACUUUUCUUGCUUUGAAAUACCAUAAUAACUCUGUCAUCACAUAAACAGUGAAAAUUGUAGUUAGAAUGCUAAAGCCCAUUUUCCCCCUUUGUUUUCUCUUUUCAUUGGUGUGUGUGUGUGUAUGUAUAAAUGAAUGAAUAUGGGAAGAGAGAAUUCUCCUCCCGUGCCAGUUAUAUAUAUGGGCAGUAGACCUUAUUAUUAACUAGAGAACACAUGGUGUUUGGACUGUUAUUGUUAAUCAUUUCUUUUGCUCAGUGUGGUAUCCAAGCUAUAAUUUUGAUGCCUUCCCUUAUGUUGGUAAUUUAGCAACCAUUGUUCUGUUUGAUAACCACAGCUUGACAGAUAUAUUAGCAGCCUAACUAAUAUUUGUAAAAAGAGUGAGUUCAAAAUUUGUUUUUACAUUUAGCCUGACUUCCAGCCAUGGAGAAAACUUUCUUUGUAAUGUGGUCACCAGGUUGUGUUUUUUUCAGGCUUAAUUUUAUGUUAAACAUUUUACAUUGGAUUAUUUCAUCUGCGUGGUUUUGUACACCAUUUGAAUUGGGAUGCUUAUGGUGAUAUCUUGGAGAAUGUAUGCUAUUUGCAGAUAAUGAAGAUUGCUGGGAAAUUUUAGCAUUUUUGUGGAGAAUUGGGUGUAUUAAAAAGUAGAAGCAAAGAUGCUGAUUUUUAAGUGGAAAACAUGAAAGCUUUUUUUUUUCUUUUCAGACUGAGUCUUGCUCUGUCGCCCAGGCUGGAGUUCAGUGGCACGAUCUCGGCUCACUGUAACCUCCACCUCCCGGGUUGUAGCAAUUCUCCUGCCUCAGCCUCCCAAGUAGCUGGGAUUACAGGUGCCCACCACCACACCCGGCUCUUUUUUCAUAUUUUUAGUAAAGACGGGGUUUCACCGUGUUAUCCAGGAUGGUCUUGAUCUUCUGACCUUGUUAUCCACCCACCUCGGCCUCCCAAAGUGCUGGGAUUACCAUGAAAGCUUUUAUUUAGCAACUGGGAAAGUACCUGUGGAGGACAAUGACUAGGGCUGUGACAGAUGAUGUGAAUCCAUAGGGCCAUGCUUCUAGGUCUUGUCUUUGAAAGUUGUAAAUUUUAGUACACCUUCAUUUACAUUUCUAUUUGAAUGUAAAUUAUAUUAUGUGAUAAAAUUCCUCUGGAGGAAAAUUCCCAAUGCAGCUAAUUUCUCUGGAGCCCCCUGCUACUAAUGCAGAAUAAAUUAUUCUUUUCAGGGAAUUUCACUGUGUCACUCUGGGUGGUAAUGCAAGGCACAUUGGGGGCUCAGCCAAAGCCUUAGUUUCAUGGAAUUCGGAGUUUGAUCAGUGUUUGGUCAUAAAAUUGUGUCUCUUUAUAGAUAUUAUAAGACUUUCUUGACAUGUUACUUCAUGGGCUUGUUUCUAUAAAGAGUGGUUUUUUUGUCUUGUUUUGUUUUGUUUUUGACACAGAGUCUCACUCUGUCACCCAGGCUAGAGUACAGUGUUGCAAUCUUGGCUCACUGCAACCUCCGCCUCCCAGGGUCAAGCAAUUCCCCUGCCUCCAACUCCUGAGUAGCUGGGACUACAGGUGUGUGGUAGCACGCCCAGCUGAUUUUUGUAUUUUUUGUAGAGAUAAGCUUUCAUUAUGUUGGCCAGGCUGGUCUCAAACUCCUGGCCUCAAGUGACCUGCCUGCCUCAGCCUCCCAAAGUGCUGGAAUUGCGGGCAUGAGCCACCGCACCCAGCCUAAAGAGUGUUUUUUAAGUUCCCUUCUAACUAUUUUUAACACCCAUUGGAUUCACUACAAAUUACAUUGUUACCAGCCUCUCUAUCAUAAUAAUGAAUUUUCUAAGCCCCUUGGUGCUAUCCUAUACCAAAUGGGUGUAAACUGAUAUAAUAUCUUCUAUCUUUGAACUUGUAAUAUAAGAGAAUAAUGAUAAUGAAGGAAAUAGUAAGAUAAUCCAAAAAUAUGAACACACGUUAAUAAUUCUUAAUAAUUGAAUCAUAAAAAUUUUCAGCUAAAAGGAAAUCUAAAUAUACUUAAAUAUAAUUAUCACAUAUCGAAGAUGAAAUUGAAUCCCAUAUAAAUGAGUUGUCCAAAUUCAUGCAAAAAGGAAGUGGAAGAAAUUGAACCCAAAUACCACAUUUAUUUCUUGACCAUUGUUUUUGUCAUCAGGCUUAGUGAAAUGUUAGCAAUAUCUUUAAAACUCUUCUACCAACUGGGAAUAUUUUUUUAAGUGGUAUCUGGAGUUGCACAUUGGGGGAAAUCACUACUAUACUUUUCUUUGUAUGAAAACAAGUGACUUAGCAUUUGCUUAAUGCUCUACAAAAAACAAAAGUCUAUGAGAUACAAAAGAAUACACGAGACUGAAAUGGAGCGUCGAAAUGGAAAUAAUGUUGUACUGGAGCCUAGACUCUGUUGGGCUUACUGUCAUCCUUGCAUAAUUUUAGAAUCCUCUGUGAACCAAGUGAAUUAGUAGUAUCUAAAAAGAAUUGAUGCCCAGUAGUAGAUACUAAAGACCCAAAAAGAUUAACCAGAAUAACGUUUAUGUAAAAAGAAGAGAUGUUUACUUUUUCUGUAGUUCUGUUAGAUUACUUGACCAAGGGGUUUCCAUAAAUAUAGUGAAUUUGACUUGGGUAAAAUGUAUUAAAAAUAAAUAACAAAUAGCUUUCAUGAGACCUUAAGGCCCAUAUAAAGGCAUAAGUCUCAGUGAUAAAAACAUUGAGUGGUUUCAUACUAUCAAUAGUGUCCUUCAGCAGAAUUGCUUUUUAUUGUUUGUAACUCAGCCAAAAGGGAAGUUAUUACCAGGAGUUUAGGGAUCUUAAGCAUCUGCAGGAGGGUUCAGAGGUUAUGCAGUAAGGAACCAUGCAGAUCAUCAACCUUAAAAAAAUAAGGCCAUCGUCAUACACUUUUGUCAAGAUAUUAAAUUUGUACAAAUAUUUGGGAAAGUAAUUUGGCUAUAAAAUUGAAAAUGCACAUAAUGUUACAGAAAUUACAUGGUUAGGUAGGCAUCCAUUCUGUGGAAAUGAAAGACAAAAUUUAAAAACAGAUGCACACACACAUACAGAUGUUUAUUGCAGCAUCAUUUGUUAAUGGUUCAAAAAAAGGCAACAUAAAUGCCCAUUCAUAUCAUGCAUAUAAAUUAUUGGUAAUAUAUGCUACAUAUUUACUAUUCAUCCUUGUCAAAAAAUAUUUGUGCAUUAAUUUUGGAAGAUGGCCAUCAUAAAUAUAGAUAAAUAUAAAGUUCAAUGUUAAUAAGUACAGAUUCUGAAGCUGGAUUACUUGGAUUUGUGUGAAAGUUUUCCUACUUCUUAGCUCUGUGAACCUAAAAGUGUUCUACUUGUCUUGAAUUUGGUGUUCUCACUUGUAAAAUGAAGAUAAUCAUAGUACCUACCAGUAAGCUUAUAUAAUCAGUUGUUAAUACUGAUUAACAGGGUUGGCAUGGGGUCAUUGAUGAGUGGAGCACAGAGUUUCGGAAGGAAGUCUCACUUAGUUUGUAUAAAUGGUAGGAAUAUGGGUGAUUGACUUUUGAAAUCAUCAUUUUUGUUGCACAGUAUUUCAGUGCAUGAAUCUGCCAUAAUUAAUACAAUAUUUCCUUUAUUGCUAUGCUUAGAUUUUUUCGAACUAUUUUUCUCAUGGAAGAGAAAGGAAGUCAUUCCAAAUAGAAGAUUCAGCAUAAAUAAUGUGUAGAGUCAGGGAUGAUCAUGAGCUCUUUCAUUGCUGGAGAUGAUGUAUGACAGGAUUGUGUGUAUAAGCUGUUUAGAUGAUUAGAUGAUGAGUAAAGAAGAGUAUUGGUGGACCUCCAAUAUUGAGCUUAGAAGAUGUUCCGAGUAAAAUGUCUUUGGAAGGAAGCAGAGAAUUGAAAGAUAUGAUUGGACAAAGGAAAUGUGUAAUAGUGAUCCAGGAUGAAGAGAAAGCAGUUGGCAAAUAAGUAAGAGGUUAGAAAGAGAAGCAAGUUUCCUAGGAUUUGAAAAUUUCAUAAAAGAGGUUUAGAAUUUUGAUUCUCUUCCUUGUGUAAUGAAUGGGUAGCUGGGCUAAGACCUUAAAAAAACCUAGACCUUAUAUAUUUGUUUUAAAGAACAGACUGUUUUUUGUAGGGGAGGAGAAUUAUCUAGAGAAGCAAAGUUUGGGAAGCAGAAAGUUGAAAGGUAAGAAAUUUGUAAUAACCAAGGUAAAAGAUAUAUUUUGAUUCUGUACUUUCAAGCUAAGGGAAAUGGUGGUAUAGGUGAAGCAAAAGCAAUUAAAUAUUGGCAGGUUUCAAAGAAAAUCUGAAAAAAGAAUAAAAAGUUUGGAUGAGCCAGAAAUGACCCUACAAUGUUUGGCUUCUGAGAGACAAAUUAAUGUCUUGCCUAUUCCUGUAAAUAAGAUUACUGUUUUUUUUGUUUGUUUGUUUUUUGUUUUGAGGAUGGAGUCUCCCUCUGUAGCCUAGGCUGGAGUGCAGCGGCGUGAUCUCGGCUCACUGCAAGCUCCGCCUCUCCCGGGUUCACGCCAUUCUCCUGCCUCAGCCUCAUGAGUAGCUGGGACUACAGGCGUGCACCACUACGCCUGGCUAAUUUUUUGUAUUUUUCAGUAGAGACUGGGUUUCACUUUGUUAGCCAGGAUGGUCUCGAUCUCCUGACCCUGUGAUCCACCCACCUUGGCCUCCCAAAGUGCUGGGAUUACAGGCAUGAGACACCGCGCCCGGCCAAGAUUAAUAUAAUCUUCUUCCCCUUACGCUGAGUAUGCCAUAAAAUGGGCACAGAACUAAUAAUUUGAUAUUAAAUGAAAGUGACUAUUUUAAUAUUAUUACAUUGCUCAUAAAUUACCACUUUAUUUUAUGAUGUUUGUGUUAACACCCUUUUUUCCUCAUGUGUCUGUGAACUUUUCUAGCACCAAGCACAUACAAAUGCCCAAUAAUCCCUGAAUAAAUGAAGGAAAAAAUUAACAAGCAAGUGCACAAACGAGACAGCAUGUGAGAGACAGCUGUUUCCAGUUGUGCUAGAGCAGGGAGAGCAAGUUGAUGUGCAGGUGAUUCCAGAUUAAGAAGGAAGCUUAAAUAAUUCAAUACGAUAAUGCUGUGUGAGUGCUUAGUGCUUGGGAGCAGCCAUUAUCAUCAUCAACGUACUUGGCCUUAAGAUCAUCAGUGGUGUUCACCUGACUAACAAAUUGUAUAGAAAACACUAGUUGCUGGAAACCAGGAUACCACUUGUAUUUUUAGUUUAUAUAUCAUUUUCAGAGACAGAAGCUCAUCAAACAUCUUCAAUAAUAUGAAAAAUUUUCUAUUGUAAAUUUCCAAGGAGUUCUCCAUUUCAUAAAGGUAGAGCAUUAACCAGAAAUUUUCAUCCAGACACAGAAACCUUCAUUUCAGUCUGCAACAGUGUUGUUCUAUGAUGUGCUUAAUGGCGUUUCCAUCCUUGGUACUUGUAUCUUAGGGCAUAUGUGACUGUUUGCCAGGGUCAACAGAAGGUCACAGUUGAGAACAGGGCAUCUGCCCAUAGCAACAAUUCAUUUGCAGAUUUAGGUCAACAAAAUAGAACAUUUCAUGUAACGGUGGCUAUGUUAACUGGCUUGAAAGUGGUUAUUAUUUCCCAGUGUAUGCAUAUAUGAAAACAAUGUUGUAUACUUUAAAUAUAUACAACUUUUGUUUGUCAAAUAUACUUCAUAAAGCUGGAAAAAAUGAAACUAAAAAAAACAAAAAGUAAUAUGUGAAAUAUACUUAAAUAAUGUUUCAAUUAUGCAGGUAUAAAGUUUAAGAAAUAUUUAAACAAACAUGUUAUUAGCUGUAAUGGAAAAUUUGCAUGAGUUUGUAGGUUAAAAUGUCAAAGUGCAAGUACAGUUUUGGAUCAUAAAAGGCCAUUUUAGAAGUGCUCCAAGCUUCUGAAUAGUAUUCAUUUGGGUUAUUCAUUUAAUUUUCUGCCUGGAAGGGACAUGUAGGGUAUUUUGAUAUACAUAUUUUAGAAACAUAUGAUAAUUAAAGCAAAUUUCAUAGAUUAACAUGCAGCCUAAACUGCAUGAAAAUGCGUAAGUGAUGCUAAUUCCUGAUAUAUUUUGGGGUAAAAUUACUGAAGACUUUUAAUCACAUGUUUUUAUAUCUUUGGAUCUUCCCUACAUUGCUUUCAAGAAGUAACUCAACAGAAUAAAGUACACAGCUGACCUUAAAUUUGCAUUUGUUAUCAUGUCAUAUUAAAUAUUUACAGAUCAUUUAUAUGUGUGUCUUGAUUCUCAUAGUGAUUUUAUGUGCUCCAAGAAGAUAUCUCUUUUAGCAUAAACAUAUACUUUACUAACAGUUUCAUCAAAUUUUAAAAGUGCGAAGUAUACAGAUUUUAAAUGCAUUUCAAGCAGAUUUCUUUUAAAGAAAUAUGCUCAUUAAGAACAAUUGAGAAUUGAUCUUGUAGCAUGCCCACAGUGUGUUUGCCUGUCGAUAUUGAGUAUUGGAAAGGUUAUCAGAUUGUUAAGCAACAAAGGAAAAUAAAUUUUGAAAGUUUCAUUGGGAAAUAGCUAAAAACAUAAGACUGUAUAAAAAAAUUAAGAGGUAUUAGUAAGAAAUGUGUGGAUUCUUCCUUCUCUUAACAUUACUGUAGAUCCUGUUUUAUUUCAGCUGUUUGUUCCCUUAUCCUUACAUUUAUCAGGAUUCUUCUGUGUUCAACUGGCUAAUCUGAAUACUAACCAUAACAAAUAGAUGUUUGGAAGCAUUAAAGUGAUGACUUUCAAAGGGGUUAUUAUCAUUUAUCAUGAAAAUGAAUUCAGCCCACUGAUGGUAAUUUAGCCUACAGAUAAAAUGAACGUCAUAUGUUUAUAAAAUGAAUUUUCAAAUGUUUAACUUUCUCAAAAUAAUAUUUCCUAAAGAUGCGAUAUUGCAUUUAAUAUGUUCACAGGAGACACUUUACCUCACUAAUCCCCAAAUUCUAUGUUUAACCAUUGUAGAAAGGUGGUAGUUUAUAGACUGGUUCCCACAAAUAUUCAAUGGACAGAAUUUCACAAGCUUUUAUGGAAAUAUUCUGUUGUAUCCCUCAAAUGUAUAGAUUGUCUGCAUUAUAGCUUGAUGGUGAUUCUGGGCUCCAGAAUCAGAUUCUCUGGGUUUGAAUCCUGGCCCCACCAAUUAAGUGCUGUGUGAUAUUGCUUCAGUUUCCUCAAUUGAUGACAGUGCUGACCUUAUAUGACUUUUGAGACGAUUGUGAGAUAAUGCGUGCAAAAGUGCUUAGAACCACAGUUCUCAUGGUUCCCAAAUGAGCUGUAGUACCGCUAGCACUACAGGAAACUCAGAGGGACACUGCACAAUAUUUUAAACUUCUGUGAAACACUACAUAGACUUCUGUCUCAUGGUAGUUUGGUUUCAGUAUUAGAUUAUACUUCAUUCCUUUUGAUGUCAUAUCUUUGCAAAGCUGAGUUUUCAUCAGUUGCUAUGACAAAAAGCAAUACCUUGUAAAAAUCAUCAUGGAAAAAGAAAUGAAGCUGUUUGUGUCUAGUUUAAGAAGUUUUGCAGUGCCCCAAUAGACACAUAUUGGUAAUUUGUGAUUAUUUAAGAAUUAACUAAAAAUAUACAUUUUGUUCAAUGUAUGUGUAUUAUUUUCUCAAAUGGUUACUAAGUUGUUAAGACAGAAAUAAUUAAAUUGCUUAGACCUGUCUACUUAACGGACAGAACUGUUAGGUGUUUUGUUUGGUCUAAAGGCACCGUGAAAACAUUACCAAGACACUGAAGGCACUACUGGAAAGUUUGGAAAUGUCUGUGCUGGCUUAGCUUUUGCGUGUGUGCCCUCAGUAAGGGUCAGUUGUUUCUGUUGAUGGUAGUGAUGAGACAGCUAAGUAAAAAGGGCUCCCUAACAGAACCUCCAACUGGCCUGCACGCUGGGAGGAGUGCACAAUGGGGCGGAGCCUUGGGAAGUUCACACCAUUUGCAGAGGGGAGGAGCCGGGCCUCUCCUGAUCCGGGAUGGUACCUGGGAUUCAGUCUGUGAGAUGAGGGUCUGUUAACAAGAACCUCUCUUGCUUUGAUGAGUUGUUUUUUUUCCUUUUCACCCAAUAAAUUCCAUUUUUCUCACCCUUCAAUGUGUCUGCAAGCCUAAUCUUUCCUGGUCAUGUGACAAGGACCCCGUUUUUAGCUGAACUAAAGAGAAAGUCCUACAACAAUAAUAGUUAGGAAGUCAAAGCCAUUUUCUUAAGCUUAACUCAAAUUCCUCUGAUCAUCAUUUUAACCCUUUUCUUCUUGUCUAAUGACAGUGAGGGGGAAAGAGAGAAAGAAUGGAAGGAGGGAAGAAAAUAAGUAAAUCUGCUGAUGGAAAUUGGGAUGUGUGACUGGAAGGGCAGAAAUGAAAGCAAUCUCCAAUGAAGGGAGUAGAGGAGCUGUUUCCUGUGAAAAACAGUCCUGUGAUGAAGAGAUUAAAGAGAAACAACAAAGUGAAAGCAAAAUACGGAUAAACAAGUCAAGUGGGACUCAGUCUGGAAGCCAGAGAAGGAUAGCUAUGCUGAUUGCUGUGUUUGAAGAACAAGAACCACUCCACAAGAUUGAGAGCCCCAGUGGAAACCCUGCAGAUCGGCAGAGCCCAGAUGCUUUUGAGACAGAAGUGGCCGCCCAACUGGCCGCAUUUAAGCCAAUUGGUGGGGAGAUUGAAGUAACCCCUUCUGCUCUAAAACUAGGCACUCCACUGCUGGUGAGGAGAAGCAGUGACCCAGUGCCAGGCCCACCUGCUGAUACCCAGCCAAGCGCUUCACACCCUGGUGGCCAGAGUCUGAAACUGGUUGUUCCAGAUUCCACGCAGAACUUGGAAGACAGAGAAGUUUUGAAUGGUGUACAGACAGAACUACUAACUUCGCCAAGAACUAAGGACACAUUGAGUGAUAUGACAAGAACAGUGGAGAUUUCUGGGGAAGGAGGCCCAUUGGGAAUACAUGUAGUGCCCUUCUUUUCAUCUCUGAGUGGAAGGAUUCUAGGACUCUUCAUCCGAGGCAUUGAAGACAACAGCAGGUCCAAGCGGGAGGGACUAUUUCACGAAAAUGAAUGUAUUGUAAAAAUCAACAAUGUGGAUCUCGUAGACAAAACCUUUGCUCAGGCUCAAGAUGUCUUCCGCCAGGCAAUGAAAUCUCCAAGUGUGCUCCUCCACGUGCUUCCUCCACAAAACCGUGAACAGUAUGAAAAGUCAGUCAUUGGCUCUCUUAACAUUUUUGGUAAUAAUGAUGGCGUUUUGAAAACCAAAGUGCCGCCUCCUGUCCAUGGAAAAUCGGGACUAAAGACAGCAAAUCUCACAGGAACCGAUAGUCCUGAAACAGAUGCAUCAGCUUCCCUGCAACAAAACAAGAGUCCCCGAGUACCAAGGCUGGGAGGAAAACCAUCCUCUCCCUCACUCUCGCCUCUCAUGGGAUUUGGCAGCAAUAAAAAUGCAAAGAAAAUUAAGAUUGACCUAAAGAAAGGCCCUGAAGGACUUGGUUUCACUGUGGUUACCAGAGACUCUUCCAUACAUGGUCCCGGUCCCAUUUUUGUAAAAAACAUUUUACCAAAGGGAGCAGCAAUAAAAGAUGGCCGCCUACAAUCAGGGGACAGAAUUUUGGAGGUAAAUGGGAGAGAUGUCACCGGACGAACCCAGGAAGAGCUUGUGGCCAUGCUCAGGAGCACCAAGCAGGGGGAGACAGCAUCGCUGGUCAUUGCCCGCCAAGAAGGACAUUUUCUGCCCCGAGAGUUGAAAGGAGAACCUGACUGCUGUGCACUCUCUCUGGAGACAAGCGAGCAGCUCACCUUUGAGAUCCCCCUGAAUGAUUCAGGUUCUGCUGGCCUCGGGGUGAGCUUAAAAGGGAACAAAUCCAGAGAAACUGGAACAGACUUGGGGAUUUUUAUCAAAUCCAUCAUUCAUGGAGGCGCUGCUUUUAAGGAUGGUCGUCUGCGAAUGAAUGACCAGCUGAUUGCAGUUAAUGGGGAAUCUCUUUUGGGAAAGUCCAACCACGAAGCUAUGGAAACACUUAGGCGGUCAAUGUCCAUGGAGGGAAACAUCCGAGGGAUGAUCCAGUUGGUGAUUCUGAGGAGGCCAGAGAGACCAAUGGAGGAUCCUGCAGAGUGUGGGGCAUUUUCCAAGCCAUGCUUUGAGAACUGUCAAAAUGCUGUAACCACCUCUAGGCGAAAUGAUAAUAGUAUCCUGCAUCCACUUGGCACUUGCAGUCCACAAGACAAACAGAAAGGUCUAUUGCUGCCCAAUGACGGAUGGGCCGAGAGUGAAGUUCCACCUUCUCCAACACCACAUUCUGCUCUGGGAUUGGGCCUCGAAGAUUACAGCCACAGCUCUGGGGUGGAUUCAGCAGUAUAUUUUCCAGAUCAGCACAUCAACUUCAGAUCUGUGACACCGGCCAGGCAGCCUGAAUCAAUUAAUUUGAAAGCCUCGAAGAGCAUGGACCUUGUGCCAGAUGAAAGCAAGGUUCACUCAUUGGCUGGACAAAAAUCGGAAUCUCCAAGCAAAGAUUUUGGUCCAACUCUGGGUUUGAAAAAGUCCAGCUCCUUGGAGAGUCUGCAGACUGCAGUGGCCGAGGUCAGGAAGAAUGACCUUCCCUUUCACAGGCCCCGGCCGCACAUGGUUCGAGGCCGAGGCUGCAAUGAGAGCUUUAGAGCAGCCAUUGACAAAUCCUACGAUGGACCUGAAGAAAUAGAAGCUGACGGUCUGUCUGAUAAGAGCUCUCACUCUGGCCAAGGAGCUCUGAAUUGUGAGUCUGCCCCUCAGGGGAAUUCGGAGCUAGAGGACAUGGAAAAUAAAGCCAGGAAAGUCAAAAAAACGAAAGAGAAGGAGAAGAAAAAGGAAAAGGGCAAAUUGAAAGUCAAGGAGAAAAAGCGCAAAGAGGAGAAUGAAGAUCCAGAAAGGAAAAUAAAGAAGAAGGGCUUCGGCGCCAUGCUGAGAUUUGGAAAGAAGAAAGAGGAUAAGGGUGGAAAGGCUGAGCAGAAAGGUACUCUGAAACAUGGUGGCCUGAGAGAAGAAGAGCUGGAGAAAAUGAAAGAAGAGCGUGAAAGGAUUGGAGCAAAACAUCAGGAGCUAAGGGAAAAGCAGGCAAGAGGUCUUCUUGAUUAUGCUACUGGUGCAAUUGGAUCAGUGUAUGAUAUGGAUGAUGAUGAAAUGGACCCCAAUUAUGCCAGAGUGAACCACUUUCGGGAACCAUGCACAUCAGCAAAUGUCUUUAGAUCUCCAUCUCCCCCUCGAGCUGGACCAUUUGGUUACCCUCGGGAUGGCCAUCCACUGUCUCCAGAAAGAGACCACUUAGAGGGUCUCUAUGCCAAGGUCAACAAGCCAUACCAUCCACUGGUUCCAGCUGACAGUGGCCGUCCUACGGGUGGAAGCACUGACCGUAUCCAGAAGUUGCGGAAAGAGUAUUAUCAGGCUCGGAGGGAAGGUUUCCCUUUAUAUGAAGACGACGAAGGAAGAGCAAGGCCAUCUGAGUAUGACCUACUCUGGGUGCCUGGAAGGGGUCCAGAUGGGAAUGCACACAACCUCCGCUUUGAAGGGAUGGAGAGGCAGUACGCAUCCUUACCCAGGGGAGGACCCGCAGAUCCUGUAGACUAUCUGCCAGCAGCACCUCGGGGGCUCUACAAGGAAAGGGAGCUUCCCUAUUAUCCAGGGGCUCAUCCUAUGCACCCUCCCAAAGGGAGCUAUCCCCGCCCCACAGAGCUCAGGGUGGCAGAUCUCCGGUAUCCUCAGCACUACCCACCCCCGCCAGCUCCCCAGCACAAAGGACCCUUUCGACAAGACGUUCCGCCUUCCCCUCCCCAGCACCAAAGAAUGCCAGCCUAUCAGGAAACAGGCAGACCAGGGCCCCGUGGGGGCAGCCCAGACCAGUACCCUUACCGAACCCAGGAUUCCCGGCAGAAGAACCCCAUGACUGCAGCCGUAUAGCUGAGUGCCACCGAGGCCAGCCCGGUCCAGAAAGGAAGGUGUCUACUCUACCUUUGCCCUUUCUAAACCUGAAGACCUCCUUGGUGUUAGGAAUUCUCCAUGUUACUGAUAAGCUUUUUCUCACUGACAUUGUAACGCAUGACUGCUAAUCAGAGAGAAAAAGAAGGGGAAGGGAAUUGGGGAGGAAAAAAAAUCAGAAGGAAGACGAAAGAUGGGGCUAUAAAAACAAAACUACCUGAUAGUUGAAACGCUUUCAGAGUUGUUCAAAUCAGUGAGAGUGGCAACGGAACACACAAACAACUAAUUAUGGAACUCUACUCUGGGGAUCCUCUCUGGCUAGAUAACCUGUGCUGAUGUGCAGACACGUGGACAUCCCCCUCUGAGACUGGCGGUCCAGAGGCAGUCUCUGCCAGGCAGCAUUACCCGCUCCGAGGUGGAGCCUCAGCCCCCUUCUUAGAGCUGUUAAGUCUAAGGUGUGGCAGAGCAGACAGAGAUAGAGGCAUCUGAAGUGAGUAUAGGUUUUUUGACUAAGAAAAAAAACAACAGCAAACAUGACUAGUGAUCUUGAAAUAUUUUGUACCGAGAGAAAGACUGCAUUUAUUUGUAGAAUUUAUCAGGUUUCUGAUACCACUCAUUGGAUGUAAACAUUUCAUGUUUCCUCACUUUUGAUAUGAAAGUCGGUAAAAUGCAGUAUUAGUCCCGGGAGGAUGUGCACAGCUGGUCAGAGCUUCCAGAAGGAAUAUCUUCCGAGGACUAAGGUGAUCAGGUUAAGAGGGUUCAACAUCCCACGGCCCUCACCUUCCUCCCUCCCACAUUCCAGGCAUGGAGAUAUCUGGUUUCAGAGUCAGCCCCAAAUCUCCUGCCUAUAAUUACUUUAACUGGGGUCUCUAAGGUUCCCACUUGAGGGCUAAAAUGUAGUUGGGAAAGAGGGCCUACUGGGGAGGUCUCACAGGAGGCAGUGCCCUGGGAAAUGCCAAGUCCAGACUCAGUGCCAAGCAGUAACCAUCUGCACUCGGGGACAGCGAGGAGCUGACCAUGGCCUCUGAUGACCAGCAGGUAUUAGAUGGAAGUGAAUGAGAGAGAGAGAGAGAGAGAGUAUGUGUGUGUGUGUGUAUGUGUGUGUUCGAACACAUAUGAUUGCCAGUAUGGAGAAUGAAAGAUUAAUAAUGCUUUCUGGAGAGUUUGAUGCAAAAGUGGGGGAAACGGAGAAAAGGCGCUAAGGCUAAAUCCAUCUGCAUUUGCUAUAUUUCAUUAGCUAAAGUCAGGUCAGGGCAGGGCCAAGGCCUCCAAUUGGCAAAGGACAGUGUUAUGGCUUUAAAAAGCUGAAACCCCAACCUCUAAGUAGAUCACAAUGUUUUCUGAGCUUUGCAGUAAUUUUCUAUGGAAACUAAAACCUCUAAAACAUACAAGCUGGCCCAAAUGAGAACACAAGCAAAAGAUGUGGAAGACAGCAAAACCUGAGCACUGGUUUGAACCAGGCACUGACAUUUGAAAUGCUUUAAGCCUUUUCACAUUCCUUCUUUAUUCCCUCCAAAAAAAAAAGUCUUGAGUUUAAUUUAGGUCUAUUUUGGCUGAGAUUAGCAUACCUCUGACUCACAGGAUUUAAUAAAUUAUAGUAUUAUUGAAUACAUAGGACAUCCCUCUACCCCAGCUUACUCUUAUCUUUUUAAUUUAAAAUAGUAUUCUGCUACCAAGAAGGAUGCAACUGCUAGUUUUAGAUGUAAAUAGUGUUAUUUACUGGACUUUGUGAUAUUAUUUUCUUAACUACACUUUACUAUGGCCCUGUUGAAAACAGACUAUCAAGUUUUUUGUCUCUGUUCUGUCAUCUCUCUUAAGCCAGGCACCUUUAGAGUGUUUGCAAUUUGUUCGAAGUGGUUGAGGAUCUCAGGCCCUGCUCACGUGAGGUGGAGUGCAGGGGAGCUACCGGUUUCCCUGCUGACCUGCUGAAUGCUACCUUCCCCUCGAGUUGAAUACACCUUAAGGAAAAUGAUAACACGAGGGACGUGUAACUUGUUUUGAAGCAUUAAAAACCAGCAGCUCUUCACUAUGUUCCAUAUUUUAACCAAACUACUGUAGACUACUAAACAUAGCCAAGCCAGAACAUUCCUUCUGGAUUAAGCCUAGGCCACUUGAGGGGCAGCCAGGGGUGAUGGUGUCAGGUGAGAAUCCUGUGUCUUGAAGGAGUGGCCUUUACAGGAAGAGUGCCCAUGUUUUCACCUGCAGCGUUGCCACCAGAGUGUGCAAUACCUCCUGCACACAGGCUCAGGGUAAACUGCUCCAAAGCUGGGUUUUGUGUUGCAUACAAAGUCAAUAAAAUAGUUGCUAAUCCUGAAUGGCAGCCAGUGAUGUGAAGGUACUAUUAAAGUGAACAAAAACUAGAUUGCAACAGUUUUCUUUCCUUGCUUGAAGUAUAACACACGCUCCAUUUGAUCCUGCCUGAAAGAAGCUAACAUUAUAUUUGUGACAGACAGAGGCUCCAUCAAGCCAAGCAACAAUUAACAGCUCAAGUGUAAGAUUUAUAAAUGCCCGUGUACUCACCCUUCAAUUGUUACCACCCAGAGGUUACAGGACUCUUUCCCAGCAUUUAGGGGAACAGGCUUUUAGAGUAUUUAGAAGACCAGGCUAUAAUCAGUAAUGUGCCUGGGAGCAGGAAAUAGCUCCCAAUUUAUUUAUGGCCUUGGGAAAACUCAAUCCGGUGUCUCCUUGUAGCUCAGAACACUAAUAGCCCCCCUGGAAGAGAGUGGCACAUUGAGCUCCAAACCCAAUCAACAUACAUCCACUUGGCUGCAGAUCUGACUGCUGGGUCAUGAAGGCCGUGAAAUGAUGUUUGCCCUCAAGUCACUAGAUAUUUUAAGAAGCCCUAUUUUUCUCCCUUUUUGCAGGAGUAGAGAGAUGAAAGAGGACAGACCAUUGAAAACUUUUAGAUGCAGGAGAAUUGAGACUUCCACAAGGGAGAGAAACACAGCCUCCCCAGAAUCCAUUAUGCCAUCGGGUUGUGGCACUCUCACCCUUGCCAUAAUACCGUUUCCUAACAAUAUCAAAUCAGUGGAUGAAAUACAAGCUCAGAAACAGGAACAUUUUCCUAAAUCAUAACCUAAUAGCAAACAAAAAUUGAAAAAACAAUUAUUCUGAAGCUCAUUAUUCUUAGAUCUGUAGAUAUAUAUGUGUUGACUCCCACAGGAUGGCACCAAGUAAAGAUCUUAAGAGCAUAGUAGGGGUUCUGAGACCGACUGUCACCCGUGGAUCCUGAUGGGGAAGAACAGAGGCUUCACUGUAGCUAUAGUUUUCCACCAAGUCAAUCAAAUUAAAACAUGACUCAUUGUCCCCUCCAAAGAUUCAUAAAAUUCUUGAGCUAAAGUGAUCUUCUGAAGAAAAGCCACCUAACAAUGUUAGGAGGCUCAUAAAGCUCAUUUCUCUUUUCCCUGGUAUGCACAAAUAUCAAGCCUAUAAAAAAGUAAUUAUUUCCCCAAACCUGUAACCACUGCAUUCGUUUUCUUUGGAGGAACAUUGUAGCAUUUCAGGAGGGUCGAGAGAUCUAAAGAGUUUGGUCUGAAUGUGUGUCUGUACAAUUCCCUUUGGCAUUAAACUCUGAAACCUACAAUCAAUGGCCUUCAAAUUGGUGUUAAAUUGGGAGAACACCCUACUGCUUUCUGAGUCUACGAGCAACAGAAAGACUGGUCUUAGUGCAAUUAGGCAGGAGGGAUUUGGACUCAGAAACAGCCACAGAAGUAUUUCUCAGCACUCCCAGUUCCUGCCAACUUAGCUGGAAACGAUGCCACAGCGAGACCAGAAAGAGGAGUCGCCUUAAGGUAUCCCUACAAAGUCACCUUUCUGAUAAAAAGGAGGGAAAAAAAAGUUAGAUAUCUAAAAUAAGCCUAGAAUCUCACACACAGCUGUGACUUCUAAGUGAAACUCUUUUCUCCCUCAUGUCCUUAAAUAGUCACAGAAUCACACACAGCCUGACUUUUAAAGACAAGCUUGGCUACAGGAAAUGAACCAACCCCAAAGACUCUUCUAACCUGUCUCCUGACUGGGCUCCUUCAGAAAGUGUUCUCCUGUUCCAUCUGUAGGGCUGCUUACUACUGGAACCUAAAACAAAACCUGUUGUUUGUACCAUCACUUUUUCUGGUGUUUCCUGUGCUUUUGUGAUUCCAAGUCUGUUCAUAAGUUCUGAAGAUAAAUUAUGUGAAAUCAUAUUUUGGCAUAUGGGGGUGGAGGAUGAAUUCUUUACAGACUUUUUAAGAUGAUCCAUUUGUACCACAGAAAACAUUUUGGAAGUUGUUAUAUAUGAGUAUAUAAAUUUUUCUUUUCAUAUUUUACAUUAAAAUAAAGCUUUAUUCAGUCAUUAA